CUCGGCUCCUAGGCUGCUCGGCGGGCGGGUGCCGGGCGCUCUGGGAGGAGAGGACUGCAGGGCCGAGCCCAGCGCACCCCGCCGCGUCCCCCGUUCCCGCCGCGCCCGCCGCGCCCGCCGCGCCCGCCGCGCCCGCCGCUCCCGCCGCGCCUGCCGCGGCCGCGACCGCGGCAGCUCAGCCUCCCGCCGAUUGUAUGUUCCAGGCCUCAAUGAGGAGUCCAAACAUGGAGCCAUUCAAGCAGCAGAAGGUGGAGGACUUUUAUGACAUCGGAGAGGAGCUGGGGAGUGGCCAGUUUGCCAUCGUGAAGAAGUGCCGGGAGAAGAGCACGGGGCUUGAGUAUGCAGCCAAGUUCAUCAAGAAGCGGCAGAGCCGGGCGAGCCGGCGCGGUGUGAGCCGGGAGGAGAUCGAGCGGGAGGUGAGCAUCCUGCGGCAGGUGCUGCACCACAAUGUCAUCACGCUGCACGACGUCUAUGAGAACCGCACCGACGUGGUGCUCAUCCUUGAGCUAGUGUCUGGAGGAGAGCUCUUCGAUUUCCUGGCCCAGAAGGAGUCACUGAGUGAGGAGGAGGCCACCAGCUUCAUUAAGCAGAUCCUGGAUGGGGUGAACUACCUUCACACAAAGAAAAUUGCUCACUUUGAUCUCAAGCCAGAAAACAUUAUGUUGUUAGACAAGAAUAUUCCCAUUCCACACAUCAAGCUGAUUGACUUUGGUCUGGCUCACGAAAUAGAAGAUGGAGUUGAAUUUAAGAAUAUUUUUGGGACGCCGGAAUUUGUUGCUCCAGAAAUUGUGAACUACGAGCCCCUGGGUCUGGAGGCUGACAUGUGGAGCAUAGGCGUCAUCACCUACAUCCUCUUAAGUGGAGCAUCCCCUUUCCUGGGAGACACGAAGCAGGAAACACUGGCAAAUAUCACAGCAGUGAGUUACGACUUUGAUGAGGAAUUCUUCAGCCAGACGAGCGAGCUGGCCAAGGACUUUAUUCGGAAGCUUCUGGUUAAAGAGACCCGGAAACGGCUCACAAUCCAAGAGGCUCUCAGACACCCCUGGAUCACGUCAAAAGGAGAAGGCAGAGCCCCUGAACAGCGGAAGACAGAGCCCACCCAGCUGAAGACCAAGCACCUGAGAGAGUACACUCUCAAAUGCCACUCAAGCAUGCCUCCCAACAACUCCUAUGUCAACUUCGAGCGUUUUGCCUGUGUGGUGGAAGACGUGGCUCGGGUCGACCUGGGAUGCCGUGCCCUGGUGGAGGCCCACGAUACCAUCCAGGACGAUGUGGAGGCCCUGGUCUCCAUCUUCAAUGAGAAGGAAGCUUGGUACCGAGAGGAGAAUGAGAGCGCCCGGCAUGACCUGUCCCAGCUCAGGUAUGAGUUCCGCAAGGUGGAGUCAUUGAAGAAGCUGCUGCGAGAAGACAUCCAGGCCACGGGAUGUAGCCUCGGAAGCAUGGCCAGGAAACUGGACCAUCUGCAAGCCCAGUUUGAGAUUCUGAGGCAGGAGCUCUCCGCAGACCUGCAGUGGAUUCAGGAGCUGGUGGGCAGCUUCCAGCUGGAGAGUGGGAGCUCUGAGGGCCUGGGCUCCACAUUCUACCAGGACACCAGUGAAUCCCUGUCAGAGCUGCUCAGCAGAUCAUGCACUGAGGAAUUUCUGGCAGGCUGGAAGCUCUAAUCGCCAGAAUCCAGUCAGUGAUGCAUCCCAAGAGGUUUGCAGAAGCAUGUUCUCAUCCACCCUGCUGCGGCCUCCAGCUAGAAUUAUCCUGCAGGGGUGUGUGUCUGUAGUAUAGCCUUCCAGCCCCUCCACAGAAUCCAGAAUUGCUGAGGUGCCAGUUAAUUCUUCAUUCUGCACCUCCCCUCACCAAUCUGGUUUUCUGGGAGGGCUCUGGCAGGGCAGCCAAGCUGUUAAAACAAUUAGAGAGUGAGUACCCCUCAGGGUCCCCUUCUGCAGAGGGAGGAUGGCUGGCCCUGGGGAAAUGCUUGAGAAUUGAUUUGUGAUGAAGGAUUUGUUCAUAUCUCACUUUCUGCCUACAUACCUUAUGGACUGUAGAUCUUGGGUAAUAUUUGAGUUAAUUAGGAAUAACUAAGUCAGCAUGGUGCUUUCCUGCUACAGAAGCAGGGAUUUACAAUGCAUAGAGAAAAUAAUAUUGCCUUUCGUUUGCAUUGAUUUUUCACUUACCAAGCACUCAUGUCUGACAAAUGACCUCACUUGGUCCUUAAAAGAACUCAGUGAGAUAGGAAGGUGGGUGGCAUUAUUAUUAUUAUUAUUUACAUGUAACUGAUGAGAAAAUUGACUCAGAGAGGGAAAAUGAUAUAGUCAAUCAGUACAGAUGAAACAGAAACCCAGGAUGCCCAUCUCUAAGAUGAGGUAUAUGGGAGAAAGUAGUAAGGCUUUGCUGUAAAUAUCUACCUUAAUAUUAAAGUCCAGGUCCCAGAGGUAAAGUAAGCAACUUCAUGUAUUCUGCCAGGUGUAGGUGGAAUGCAUACACCUGCAGAUGAUUGUCCCAGGAGCUCUGUCCCAGAAGGCAAAGUCAUUGUCCCUACCCAUCCCUGUCUCUGUCUGAAGACCAGCCUGCAAGCAGGAGAGAAGGAAGGAAGGAGUCUUCCCAUUCUCCACCCUUUCUCCUCUUCUGGCUAACGGCCCCAACUCUGUGUCGAGAAUAAAGGCCAGAAGGUCCUCAACAGGAGGUUCCUUUUCUUAUGUACCUAGGCCAUUGGGCCUUGAAGGCCUAAGAAGUUCCGUGAGGGUUUUUGAAAAGGGCAAACAUAAAGAUGGGGAAGCGCAAGGCCACAUGGUCGUUUCAUGACCCAAAGCUUUGAGCACCCCUCCCCAAGGAUUAUAAGAUCUCAUCUCCCUUUCUCUGGGGGAGGGGACAGUCAACCAACUCAUGUCAACAGAGCAUGGCAUAUGAGCCUAGUGCUGAGCUAGAAGCUUGUGGGUAGGGGCAUAACUUGUAUAGUUCAAAGUGUCUUCAUGGCCUCACAAAACAUCCCUAUCUUAGAGGCAGACUAAACGAUAUUCCCAAUUUAGAGCUGAGGAAACAGGGAGAGGAUGGGAUUUUCCCAAGGUCACAUCAUUAUGGCAAAAGUAGAGACCUUCUAAUGACAAGUCUGUUGCUCUUUCUGCUUCCCCUGGCUGCGCCAGGCUCCAGAAGUUUACUCCCUGCUUGUGGGGGCAGCUCACACCUGGAUUCAUCCAUCCAUUUAUAAAUUAUACUUAGGCACCAACCAACUUCCAGAUGCCCGGCUUGACUCUGGGGAUACAAUGUUUAGUAAAAAUAGGCCUGAUUCCUGUCUCACGGAGUGCUCAGUCCAGCGAAGGAUUUGAACAUUGACCAAGAAUCACAGAGAGAUAGAGCUGCAGCUUGUGUUCAUGCUGGGAGAGAAGCACAUAGCACUGCAGGGGCCUGCCGUCAGGGUCUGACAGCAUCGGGGGAAGCGUCCUGAAGCAGUGACACUGGAACGGAGGUCAGCUAAGCCAACCAGGGAGAGAGAAGUUUCCCAACAGAGCCAUCAUACCAGAGCUCUGUGAUGAGAGGCGGUGUGGAAGGUUGAGAAUGUGAGGACUGAAAGCUGGAGGGGAGAGAAUAGGAAUACAGUGCGGAAAUGACCGGAGAACAAGCAGGAGCAGCAGGGCUUUGGCCAUGUGGAAGAGCUCUGCCCUUAUCCCGAAAGUCAUGAGAAGCCAGCGGGUUCCAGGUGCUGGGGAGGGAAUGCCCCGUGAACAGCUCAGACAGGAAGUGGUUUAGGACAAGACAGGAAAGCUUCAUCUCAUGAAACCAUUUCUUCAGAAUCCUGUCUCCUUUUCUAUAUGCAUGAAGGAUCAUUUCAAAUAUCAUAUACAAUAUUUGUAACAGAAACUUACUUCAUCAGCUAUGAGAAACCGUGGUGAUAAGAUGCAUCAUCAUUUUAUGGACCACUAAGAAAAAAGGCCCAAGAUGGGGCGUCUAAUAGGAAACUCUCUCUACCCCCACCACAUAAAGCUGUGAUGCCCUCAAUGAGAGGGUAAAUGAGAAAUAGAGCCACCAUGCAGAAAGGGGGAGCAAGGAAACCCAUGCAUCUCAACCUUGACACUAAAUGGGGGUGAAAAAUCCUUCCCUGAGAACAGGAGUCCCAAGCCGGUGGUACUCAUGCAGGUUUGCUUUCUGAAUUUGCACUAUCAGUGUGAUCCAAAAGAACAUCAAGCAGAGAGUGUAAUGUCCAACAGUCUGAGGCUGGGUGGCCCUGGAUGGCUGGCAAAAACAGUACUAUCCUCUCCCGGAGCACCUGCCUUCUGUCCGGGCCAACAGUAAGAAUAUGAUACCAUCAUCUGGGAGAUGCCUCCUGACUUCAGAGAUCCAAAAAUGUAUAUCUUGGAACCAAUGAAAGAUGGCAAAAGCUCCAUUUCCUACAUCUUACCCCAGAGAAUUGGUUCAAAUGACCUGUCUACAGUCUCUCCAAGGUCUUACCUGCCCUGUCACGGGAAGUUGUAUACUUGUUUGGUGCUGAGACACUGCAAAUAUUAAAUGUCCCUUUGGCCGUGUUAACAGACCUUGACCUUCACACAGCCAGGUUUCUAAGGAGAGGAAGCCACUGAUGGGGCAACACAGGGCAAGCUUUUUAGUGAAGGUCAAAAUAGAAUGCAGGCCCAGUGUGGUGGCUCAUGCCUGUAAUCCCAGCACUUUGGGAGGCUGAGGUGGGUGGAUCACUUGAGGUCAGGAGUGUGAGACCAGCCUGGCCAACAUGGAGAAAUCCUGUCUCUACUAAAGAUAUAAAAAUUAGCUGGGCAUGGUGGUGGGUGCCUGUAGUCCCAGCUACUCAGGACACUCGGGAGGCUGAGGCAGGAGAAUCGCUUGAACCUGGAAGGCGGAGGUUGCAGUGAGCCAAGAUCACGCCAUUGCACUCCAGCCUGGGUGACAGAGUGAGACUCUGUCUCAAAAAAAUAAAAAAUAGAAUACAGUAAAAGAGUAAAAUGUUGGCAAUGAUUUGAAUGGGGAAAAUUGGGAAAAGGGAGGGAGAAGUGGUUGUUUUAGAAUCAUGAUCAGCUAUACACAGUGCUGAGAGUCACCCAUUUAGUUGGCCGUGAGCUGGACUCCGAACUCUAAGUGGUUUUCCUUAUAGCAGUGACAUCGUCCUCUCUAUGCUCAUGUCCAGUCACUGUAACUGUUUCUCACUUAGACGUGUCGUAAACAGACCUUUUUCUGUACAAAGAGCUUCUAAAGACAAAUGAAAGAGAGUUGAGAAAUGCCCCCAAGUCUUUUGGGGAAAGCAGAGGAGACCAUGACCUUCCUCUGUGUCCUGGCCAGCUGAAGUCCCGUCCUUCCAUGGCAUUGGAACCUGAUGCUGGGGGAGCCCGGGGGCCUGUGGGAUGCAGCCACAGGACCUGCUUAUCUCUGCUCCCCACACGCCCUCAGCUGACUUUUUACAACAGUGUGGAGGGCUAACAAUGGCGGGAAGGGCUGUGAGAAUGGACUGUUUCGCUGGUGCCUAGAGGAAGGAAGGCUUGUGGGUGCUGCUCUGUGGGCAGGCCCCUCUGCCAUUGAGGAUUUUUAAUUCACCAAAUUGCAAUUUUUUUGGUGGGGGAGCCGCACAGAGUCUCACUCUGCCGCCCAGGCUGGAGUGCAGUGGCAUGAUCUCGGCUCACUCCAACCUCUGCCUCCCAGGUUCAAGCAAUUCUCCUGCCUCAGUCUCCUGAGUAGCUGGGACUAUAGGUGCGCAGCACCAUGCCCGGCUAAUUUUUGUAUUUUUAGUAGAGAUGGGGGUUUCACCACAUUGGUCAGGCUGGUCUCGAACUCCUGACCUCAGGUGAUCCACCCACCUCGGCCUUCCAAAGUGCUGGAAUUACAGGCGUGAGCCACUGCACCCAGCCCAGACUGCAAAUAAAAGGUCGGCUUCUGUGCUCUGUUCAAACACCAUCCUGGGCUGUUUGGGAGGGGAAAGUGAGUGUAUGACAUCGCCCUGAAUAACAAUUCUCAAGGAAGCUGGCAAGCUGGCCCUUGGGGAAGGCAGCUGCCUGUCCCUGCUGUGAGGCAGGUGCUCACAGCCUAGCAUUGCCUGACUGUGUGUCAGAAGGUGGGGUGAUGGUUUGGUAAUCGAUGAUUCUGCAGCUGUGGGAGCCUGGCAGUGAAGGGAUGGAGCAGAGGAAUAAUGGCAGAAAGAGCUGGAGUCUCCCCCAUGGGCCCCCUCCCCUCCCUUACAGGUGAUCAUGAAGAUGGUGGCUUCCUACCUCACUCCAUCACGCAGCACAGGUGGCCCGGCCCUUGCUGGAGGUGGCUGUGUGCCCAGCUGUCACCCCUACUGUCAAUCUUCUGUAAAUGUCUGUGGGACUGGAUGCCUUUUUUCCUUGGUCCGUGAAAUUCCUGACCCAGCAGUGGGCAUGUUCACGUUGCAAAAGGGUCCAGUCCCGUUGAACAAACACUGAUUGUGCUCUGGCUCAGGGGGAGGUGACAGACAAGGACAAGAUAACCUCAAAUAAAAGAUUCAGUGUCUGGGGCAGAUGGGGACCCAGCCAACUAGAUUGGAAAAGCUAUGGUGAGUGAUAAAAUAGAGCUUCCUCAUCUCCUAGAAAUCAAAGGAGAGAGGAAUUCUGAUUGAGAAAGGGUAAGAGGGUUGCAGAGAAGAGAGGCCUUCCCAGGGACGCCGUCCCCACCAGUGACCGCCCUCCUCCACUCCCAAGCUGUGUCCCUUGAGGAAGGCAUGAGUAAAAUCUGGAAGGGGGGUGGGGCUGAGCCAAGAUUGGGGUUAGGAACUUGGAACAGUUGAAUGGAGAUUAAAGAGAGGGAGAUUACACAGAUUUAAAAGAGUGUUUUAAACUUUUUGUUAUGGUCCCCUCAGCAGGAAAAUUGCCAAAACUUGCACAGAAGUAUAAGGAAUGGGAUAGUGGAUUCCAGGACCUAUGACCCCGCUCCAGCAGGAAUCAAGUCAUGCGGGUCCUCUUUCAUUCAUCUCUCCCAUUACUUUUCUUCUGGGGUAUUUUAAAGCAAAUUUCAGACUUAUUUAACUCAUAAGUUCUCCAGCAUAAAUCUCUGCUAAGGAUUUUCUUCUUCUUUUUUUCUUUUUUUUUUUUUGAGACAGAGUUUCACUCUCGUUGCCCAGGCUGGAGUGCAAUGGCGCGAUCUUGGCUCACUGCAACCUCCAUCUUCCAGGUUCAAGCAAUUCUCCUGCCUCAGCCUCCUGAGUAGCUGAGAUUACAGGCACCCACCACCACACCCAACUAGUUUUUGUAUUUUUAGUAGAGAUGGGGUUUCAUCAUGUUGGCCAGGCUAGUCUUGAACUCCUGACCUCAGGUGAUCUGCCUGCCUCGGCCUCCCGAAGUGCUGAGAUUACAGGCAUGAGCCACCGCACCCAGCCAGGACUUUCUUUUUAAUACAACCCCAUGCCAUUAUCACACUUGACAAAAUCAGCAAUAAUUCCUUCAUCUCAUCUGGAUUCCCAUUCCAUCCUCACAUGUCCCCACCACUCCCAACAGUGUCCCAUUACAGCUGGUUUGUUCAAAUCAGGAUCCAAACAGUCCACAUGUGGCAUUUGGUUGCUACGUCUCUCAAGUCUCUUGGGUUUUAUAACAGUACAAAAGGAAGAACCUUUGAAGCUUUUCCUGGGGACAAAAAAUUGCUCAGAAAACUGAUGGUCCCAUAGAAGAAUAAAAAACAGAGCGUAUCCAUGUCAAGACCUAACUCAGAAAUGUGAGACCAGGCCAAGCAAGGAAAGGAAUGUUUCUGCCUCCUUCCACUGGCUUGUUCACUGUAGGGGGCAGCCUUCAGGCUCACAGCCUUUCUGCAGCUGUCCCUCCCACUUAGGAGGAGGCAGAGCCUCAAGCCUCCCACAAGCCCCAUGUGCUCCUUUCCUGGGAAAACAGGUGGGUGAAGGCAGCAGAGCCCAGGCUUCAGCCAUCAAAACAUCCAGCGAAGGGGAGGGGUGGAGGGGUGCCACCUAUAAAACUCCAUUGAGGGAAGGGCAGCGGGGAGGGGUCCUGGGCAGGAGAGAAGUGGGUGUGAGAGUGCCCUGGCUUUCACUGGAGUAAGGGGCUGGAGAGAUGGCACAGAUGGGGGUUGGAGGUGCAAUCUGCUUGCAGUUCCUAAAGAAGACCUAGUAUCUAGAGAAAAUCGUUGUGUGGGGGGUGGAGUUGGGGGAGUCGCCUCUUCAGUAAAGCCAGGAUUCCUUUUUCAUGCCUUAGCAGCGGCUGCUGCUUCCUGCCCCUGCCUGUGGAUGUUGGUACUGACCUGGCACACCCCACUGGACUUUUUCAAAGGCAUUUGCAGCUGCAUAAACAAAACUUGACUACCCCACA